AGCUUUUCUCUGUGACAUGUCGCGGAGUCGCCGGUAGGGUUCGGUGUGGCGAGGGGGACCUGCUUCUCUCUUUGUGAGAACCAGGGAGUGAGGGAGGAAGGAGGCCAAGGAGGAGGCCAGGACUGAGCAAGGACUAAAGUAAGACUGAAAGGGGAGGUGAGGGGUGGACUGGUUGUCGGCAGCAGCCGGUACCGGAAGUGGCGGCAGCAGCUGAGGCGACGCACCGUGAGGCAGCUGCUUGACUAGGCCACAGCCGCCAUGGCGAUGAAUUUUGGGGACCAUGCCAGCGGCUUCCGCCACAAUGAUGUGAUCAGGUUCAUUAACAAUGAAGUCCUCAUGGACGGCAGCGGCCCAGCCUUUUACGUGGCCUUCCGCUCGCGGCCGUGGAACGAGGUAGAGGACAGCCUUCAGGCCAUUGUGGCCGACUCUCAGGUGCCGCGCGCCAUCAAGAGGGCCUGUACCUGGAGCGCUUUGGCUUUGAGCGUGCGAGUGGCCACGAGGCAGCGGGAGGAGCUGCUGCACCACGUUCGGCGGCUGCAAAGGCAUGCGGAGGAGCGCCAGGCGACCUCCUGGGCUCUAACGUCCCAGCUGCAGCAGCUGCGCCUGGAGCAUGAGGUGGCGGCAACACAGCUGCACCUCGCGCAGGCUGCCCUGCAGCAGGCGCUGAAUGAGCGUGAUGGGCUGUACGGGAGGCUGCUCCAGAUCGAGAGGUUUCCCCAGGCCGCUCCACUGGCCCAUGAAAUAAUGUCUGGGCCGCAAGCAGAGCAGAAUGGGGCUGCGGCAUGUCCCCUGGCUACAGAGCAGCAGAGCGAUAUGGUGGCCAUGGGGACACAUGCUAAUGCCCAGAUGCCAACCCCGACAGAUGUUCUUUAUGUGCCAGGACCUCUGAGUCCCUGGGCCCAGGGCAUGCAACCCCCUCUGCCAGUGCCACAUCCAUUCCCACACCCACCACCAUUCCCAAUGAAAUUCCCAUCCUUGCCACCUCUACCACCUGCUGUAGUCACGGGGGCAGAAGCAGCAGCAGUCCCACUUCAGAUGCCUCCUACUGAGAUCCACCCACCUUGCCCGUGGCCUGCAGUGGGCUUCCAGGAGGAGAUGGCCCCUCUGUGGUACCAGAGAAGCUACAUCCAGGAGGAAGAUUCCAAAAUCCUUCAGGGGUCAUUCCCCUUAGGAGACAGCAGAAGCCACAGCCAGGGAGAAGGUUCAGAGAGGUCCCAAAGAAUGCCCCUCCCCGGGGACAGUGGGUGCCACAACCCGCUGUCAGAGAGUCCCCAGGGGACAGCCCCACUGGGGAGCAGCGGAUGCCACUCCCAGGAAGAAGGUACAGAAGGACCCCAGGGGAUGGAUCCCCUGGGGAACAGAGAGAGACAAAAUCAGAAAGAAGGUCCAAAGAGGGCCCGGAGGAUGCACACCCUGGUGUUUCGCAGGAGCCACAAAUCAGAAGGUCCAGAGGGGCCCCAGGGGACGGUCCCCCAGGGAGACAGCAGAAGCUACAGCCAGGAAGGAUGUUCAGAUAGGGCCCAGGAGAUGGCCACCCUGGUGUUUAUCAGGAGGUGCAAACCAGAAGGUCCAAAGAGGCCCCAGUGGACUGUCCCCCUGGGGGACAGCAGAAGUCAUAUCAAGGAAGAAGGCCCAGAGGGGCCCCAGAGGAUUGUCCUCCAGGGAGACAACAGGAGCUAUAGCCAGGAAGGAAGCCCAGAGAGGGCCCAGGGGAUGGCCACCCUGGUGUUUAGCAGGAGCUGCAAACCAGAAGAAGGUCCAGAGAGGCCCCAGGACACUCCCCUGGGGGACAGCAGAAGUCAUAUCAAGGAAGAAGGCCCAGAGGGGCCCCAGAGGAUUGUCCUCCAGGGAGACAACAGGAGCUAUAGCCAGGAAGGAAGCCCAGAGAGGGCCCAGGGGAUGGCCACCCUGGUGUUUAGCAGGAGCUGCAAACCAGAAGAAGGUCCAGAGAGGCCCCAGGACACUCCCCUGGGGGACAGCAGAAGUCAUAUCAAGGAAGAAGGCCCAGAGGGGCCCCAGAGGAUUGUCCUCCAGGGAGACAACAGAAGCUAUAGCCAGGAAGGAAGCCGAGAGAGGGCCCAGGGGAUGGCCACCCUGGUGUUUAGCAGGAGCUGCAAACCAGAAGAAGGUCCAGAGAGGCCCCAGGGCACUCCCCUGGGGGACAGCAGGAGCCAUGGUGUCAGAGAAAGCCCAAAGAAAUGGCAACCUCAGAGGCAGAAGGCCAAGAAACCAAAAGUGAAUAAAGUCUCGGGAUCCCAGCAGCAGGAGAAGCCUGCCUCAUUUCCAGUUCCAGUGAAUUGGAAAUGCCCAUGGUGUAAAGCCAUUAAUUUUUCAUGGCGUACGGCCUGCUAUAAAUGCAAGAAAGCCUGUGUGCCAUUUGAGAGUGGAGGACAAACUCAGUGAUUUCAGGAAGGUAAGUAAGAAUGGACACACUUCAAAGAGAAAGCAAUUUCCUAAGACCCUCUUCUGAUUAAAGUAUAACUUAUUUACUUCACAGAAAAAUUGAACCCCAAAUUAUGGAGAAAAUUAAAUAAAAUAAUUUAUUAUCCCAUUACCCAAAUUAGCCAUUUUAAAAGUUGUUUUGGAUACACAUACAUACAAAUAUAUAUGCAUUUAUAUUCUCAUGUUAUUCAUUUACUUGAACAGAGAUGGACUACUUUUGAUUUCUCCUGAUUGCAUUUAAAUUUUGCAGGUGGUGGAUUCUGGAUGGCCGAUGCUGAUUGGUUAAUACCCUGGAGAAGCUGAAGUCAUGAAGCCUUUUCUUUUCCUUUUUGUUUCACUCCUUUUCCUGAAAAAGCCAUGUAUGUGGCUGGGAGCAGUUGUGUGAUUUUAGAGUUAGAAGAUAUGUUGAAUUUUAGGAACAGUACUUUUCCUUGAAAAUGCUGUUAUUCCUUUGGAAACAAAUUUUAGAAUCACCACACUUCCUUGAAAAUGCUAUUAUUCCUUUUGAAACUACUGCAAUCUUCAUGUUUUCUUCAUUUUGCUUUGUUGGUUUUAUAGGUGAGGUUCUGUUUUUGUAUCUCAGCCCCACCAAACUUGCUUGUUGCUGAAGAAGCUGAACCUGUUCCAUUAGAAGAUCUUCCAAAGCCAAAAGAAAGUGAGACUGACUGCAGACUUACUGGCUGCAGCAGAGAGGAGUAAGAGGAAGUCAGAGAAGAAGAGAUGAUUUGACACUCAUUGGGGGAAAAGGAAGAGCAGAAUUGUUUUGUUAGAAUUGAAUUUUUCCACUGGGACAAGGAAUUAACUUGGAAGAGUUUGGGGGGUUGUGUUCAAUUCUGUAGAUGGUAGCAACUUUGAUGAAUUUCGUUUAGUUUGUUAAAUAGUUAUUGUCUAAUAUGUGUUAGGAGCUAGACUUAUAGGUUAUUAUUUGGUGCACACAUCAUAAUCCUUGUUGCUGAGUUGGUUAGAAGAUAGGAGAGAGCAUAAUUUGGGAUACAAAUUAGAUCAGGGGUAUCUUCUUUGCCUUGCAUGUAGUGUUGCCUUAGGUAAAACCAAUUUAAAUAACAUCUAGAUCCAUUUUUGCAGUUUUGUGGGCAAUGUGAAAGAGACUUGCAUGAAAGGUCUUGAGUAACCAAACUGCUAGUCUCAUUGGUUUGCAGGUGAGACAAAUAAGCAGUGGCAAAGUUCAGGAAAGUGGUCUUACAGAAGUGCAGGCAGGGCUUUUCUGAUUGUCUGCUGAUUUCCUCCUUUGAGAGGGACAGAUAUUUUCCUGGCUGCCAGUAAGCCUGCCUGAAAGACCACUGGGGUGUCUUGAAGAAAGACAGUGCUCUGAGGAGUAUUCACUACACACUCCAGCCCUCAGCCUCGGGCUGCCCCCAUUCCAAGUCCCUUUCUAGUCAAUAGGUGGAUGAAGAACAAAAUGGAUUUCAAGGACAGACAGACAGACAUAAGGGCUGUGGGCUAUGGAUGGUGUUUCUCUUGAGAGGACUAAUUGGGUUAAAAAUAAAACUGGACAGGGGCGAGCACUCUUGGGAAUGCCCCUGGACCCUUCCUCUUUGGCGUGUUCUCUGCAGGCUCCCCCAAGGCAGCUGCUGCAAGGCAAGGAGGGAUCCAGGGUAGAGCUCAGGGAUGGUGGGUUAGAUCUGCCUCCAGUCCAAGCUAAAGAUGUCUUCAAGUUUCCCUGUAAGAUCCCGCCCAGCUCACCAAAAUCAACCUUUGUCAGGGGUUUUCUGAUCCUAACUAGUAAUAAAGAGUGUGCACUGGA